GAACAAUUUAUCUGCACGAAUACCCCGUGCUACCAGAAUGGCUGUCUCAGUACUUCGCCUGACAGUUGUCCUGGGACUGCUUGUCUUAUUCCUGACCUGCUAUGCAGACGACAAACCAGACAAGCCAGACGACAAGCCAGACGACUCGGGCAAAGACCCAAAGCCAGACUUCCCCAAAUUCCUAAGCCUCCUGGGCACAGAGAUCAUUGAGAAUGCAGUCGAGUUCAUCCUCCGCUCCAUGUCCAGGAGCACAGGAUUUAUGGAAUUUGAUGAUAAUGAAGGAAAACAUUCAUCAAAGUGACAUCCUCAGUGCCUCACAGUCUUGAUGCAGAAGAUAUGCGUGCAUAACCAACUAAACAUACUCAACACGGUGCAGCAUAACAGAGGCACGGACAUGGGAACAUGGGAACCAGCACAAAGAACCAUUCAUGCUCCCUCGGAAAUCCGGAAAGAUUUCUCUGAUGUAAUAAUAUUUGAUCCAUGACUUGAUGAAUGAUAAAGGAUUUGAAGACAUGGAGAAGGAGAAGGAAGGGCAUUUCAACCACAGAAGAAAGCUUAAACCAAAACUCAGACUAUGGCAAUGCUUGACAUUCAAGGAUAGCCUUAUAAUCCUUCAAACUUACCUACCUUUAUUAAGAAACAGAUUUCAUUAGGAUACCUUCCAUGCUUGGUCCUGCAUAAAUGCUACCUCAUUGAAUCCUCAUACUUAGUACAAAAAUUAGAUAUGAUUAUUCCCUUUUGAAAUGAUGCAAUUGAGAAUCUGACAAGAUCACCCAGUUGAGUAACGCUGGAGCCAAACUCGAACAAAAGUCUGUGUGACUGAUUUCCUUUUGUAUUUAUUUUGAGAGUGAGAGGAAUUACUUUCUUUUUAAGAAAAUUAAUUUUAUUUUAUGUUCUGGGAUACAUGUGCAGGACAUGCAGGUUUGUUACAUAGAUAAACGUGUGCCAUGGUGGUUUGCUGUAUCUAUCAACCCAUUACCUAGGUGAGAGGAAUUACUUUUUAAUAUGUACUAAUUGACAGAAUGUUUUCUUCAAAAUUUAGAUCCAAAAAUUAUUAAAGUGGCAUAUGUUACCAUGUGAGAGGGAAAAAUGAGGGGAAUAUGGAAAUGUGUAUAUACUUCUAAAAGUUAACAAUCUCCCACACUAAUCCGAUUAUUCCCAAACCAGCCAUAUCAGCAACCAAUAUUGUUGCUGUUGUCCCUGACUGUUCAAACAUAUCCAAACAUAUUCACAUGUAGAGUGGGGUUUGGGUGAGUGCUUUACUCUGCAGCUUGACUGUCACUGAAUAAUUUCUCAUGGCAUUUAGUUUAGGUAAACAGAUAGAAAUCUUUAAAAAGCUAUUCAAUAUCUCAUUAUUUCCCUAUUGAUAGACUUUCAUAUCAUUUCUAUUUUUUCAGCUUUUCAAAGGAUUCUGCAAUAAACAAGCUUAUAUGUAUAAGCACAUGCACUAAUAUUUAUAUAUAAAUAUUUUUAUUUAAUGUUUUUAUAAAAGGUUUUCAAAAAUUGAAUUGCAAGAUCAAAGGGCAUUUUAAAAAAUGCUAAUGGACAUUGUGAAAAAGCCUUCAAAAUGUAGCCACUCCCUUAUUGGCCCAAAUGGACACUUUAUGGACUCACAGCAUAUAAGUAAUUUUCUAAACUUAUAACUGAUGUACAAAAACUGCAUGCAUUUAAAGUAUACACUUAAAGAAUUUAAACAUAUGCAUAUACUCCCAAAACCACACAAUUUAAAUACUGAACAAUCUUGGAGCUCACAAAUAAGUGGGAGAUACAAAAAAUCAUCAGAUAAUCCUACAUAAACCUAUAAUUACAUUUUGAGAGACUUGCUUGGGAAGGAAGGAAGAUGGUUCUCUUGGAAGCUGUCACAGAUGUGUAUCAACUGGGUGAAGGAAGGUUCCUAAGGAAGGGAGACAUGUGCUGAGAUCUCAAAAGAGAAAUAAUAAAGUGGUUGAAUAGGACAAAAUUCAUAAGGCAAUGAAGGAGAAGAGGCAUUUAUAGUUGAGUGAAUGGCAUUUGCAAAAGCCCUGUGCUAGGUAUACUGUUCUCUAGCCAUGAAGAAACGUCAAGGUGGCUGGAAAGCAAAUAAGAAGGAAGAAAGUAAGUCUUACAGGACCUCAUAGGUUAUGGUCAGGAUUUUAUUCUUAAAUCCAAGAACAAUGGAAAGCCACCAAAGGAUUUUGAGCAUUGGAACACAUAUGAUCAUUGUUGCAUUUUAAAAAUAUCAGUUGGCUGUUGUGCAGGCUAGACAGAGGGGUCCAGAGUAAAGCAAGAAGCCAGCCAAAAGCUCUUGAGCAAGGGAGGGUCAAUGCAGACAGAACCAUGUGGAAGGAUUCAAGAGAAUAUUAAGACAUUAGGUUGACAGGACAUGGUGAUUAGUUCUACAUGACGUGUCAGGGAGAGGGAAGUAUCAGGAAUGACUCGUAGGAGUCUGACUAAUGCAAGUGGAUAUGGUUGCAUAUGCAGUGUUGCCACUCAGGUAUAUGGAGAACAUUGGAUACAAAAUUUCCCAAGGCUUUUCUGGGCUCUUAGGAUAAAUACAGGGCCAUGACCAUGACACCUAAUGCAUGGUUUGACCUUGGCUUGUGUCCCUGUGCUCCUGCUGCCACCUGUGCACUGAAACACAGGUGAUGUUUCAGUUCUUUGAAGAAGCCAAGUUCUCCUUAUCCUCAGGAUAUUCAUGCACUUAGUACCUUCCACACAGAAUAUUAUUUGGUUAAGAUGGGUUCUUCCAACCUCAAGUCCCAACUUGGCAUGUCCAUAGAAAUGACCUAAAAUAAACAGGCAAUCUCUUGUCACUGUGACCUUUCUUAGGAUCCUAUUCUUUUCCUUUAUUGUUAUUAUCAUAACUUAUAAUUAUCCUUUUACCCAUGUUUAUUUGUGUGGUUUCUAUCUCUCCCUUUACACUGUGAAAUCUAUGGAGAUAUGGGUCAUGACAAUUUAUUACUGUAUGCUUCCUGUCCAGCAAAGAUCCUGCAACUAAUAUUCAAUAAUUAUUUGCUGAAUCGAAAAUAUAUGGAGGAAACAAUGAAUGACCAAUAGCUAUCACUGUUAUUAUGGUCAUUGUCAGUAUCAGAAAACAAGUUCUCAUUUGAUAAUGAGAGAGUUAAGGACAGAACAAAGAAUGCACCAUUUAACAAUGCUUGAAAUGAAGUCAGAGGUAGUUACUAGAAAGGGGGAGCAUCAGGUAGUUGCCAUUUAGUUGUGAAUCCCCAGUGAAAAAUUUAAUGCAAUAGAAGGUGCUGAUAUUUCUCAUUAUCUACCUUGCAUAUAUACACAAAUGUUUUCCUUGAUUUUGCUAAUAAUGAGCGCCCUCUGCUGUCUUUAAUCUGCCUCAAUAGCCUGCGAGCUCUUCAUCUGGUUGCUUUCUAAAAUAAAAAAUAAUGUAGCAAAUAAAUUGUACUUACCUGUCUGGUUGUACUGCCUAUCUUAGACAUGAAACUAAGAAAUCAUAUAAUUCAUACCUUGCAUGGCUUGACCCUCCAGCACAUAAUAAAAAGGGAUUUACAGCUAGCUUAGGGAGAACAAUCAUACCCUAGGCAUUGUCUUGGGUCCCUAAUCCCAUCUUUGGAAAUGGCACUUCUCCGACCUCAGUCACCUGAGAUACCAACUGUUCUUCCCCAUUGAAAUGUGUGACUAGUUAUCAAAAUUUUAGACACCAUGUAAUUCUGGACCUUGCAUUUCCACUUUCAAGGUUUUUCUGAAGACAUAAAGACAAAAAUGUAUGCAAAAUAUGCAUGCUCACUAUAGCACUUUUUAUAAUAACAAAAAAUAUAAUUAGAUAUUAGAAACAAUAUAAUAUACAUUAUAUAAAUUAAAUUAAUAUUCACAUAGAUAACAAUUUAAAUAAGGCAUAUGUCAUUCAUAUGUGCAAUGUAUCAUUCAUGUAUGUUUGUAAAUAUUUAGAAAAUGUCUUGAAAAAAGCACAUCAAUGUGAACAGUGGUUUCCUCUAAUUUGUGGAAUUUAUGGAUGAAGAGAAUGAAAGUUACAUAUAUGCAUAUAUGUAACUACAGUUAUACAUAAUUAUAGUUGUAUAUAAUUAUAUAUAACAUGUUAAUUAUAUUCCAUAUGAUUAUAUGAUAAUUAUAUGUAUAUAUUUCUAUAUUCUGAUGAUCUUUAAAAUAAUUUUUAAACUUUUUAAGAUAACUAUAGAUUCACAUGAAGUUUUAAGAAAUCAUACAGAGCAAUCCAGCAUAUUUUCUACCAAGUUUCCUCCAAUGGUAGUAUCUUGCAAAACUAUGCUGCUACAUCAAAACCAGUAUGCUGACAUUGAUACAGGUAAAACACAGAAUAUUUCUGUCCUCAUAAGGAUCUCUCAUACAGCUCUUAUAUAACACACUCACUUCCUUCCUGCCCCCAUCGUCUCCUUAACCCCUGGAAAUUACAAAUUUGUUCUUUAUUUCUAUAAUUUUGUCAUUUUGAGAAUGUUACAUAAAUAAAAGUAUACAAAAUUUAACCUUUGGGGUUUGACAUUUUUUCACUCAGCAUAAUUCUCUAAGGAUGCAUCCAGGUUACUGUGUAUAUAAAUAGUUUGUUCUCCUUUUUUGUUGAAUAGUAUUUCUUUACAAAGAUGUCCAAAAUUUAUCCAUUCAUCCACUGAAGAACAACUGUGUUGUUUCCAGUUUUUGGCUACUAAAAUAAAAUUGUUAUGACCA